GUCUGCUCCAGGUGCUAGCCAGGCAGGCGCAGCCGUGGCCGGCUAGGGCUGGAAGUGUCAGCGGCGGCCGCGGGCCCGGCAGAAGGCCGAGUAGGAGGGACCACGCGCCGGGGGCCGCGAUCUCUGGCAGGGGGCGGUGUGCCAGCGGAGCACCAUGCACAUAGGCGCCCAGCGCCCCAACUACCCCUCCCGAGGAAAAGAGGCCGGGGCCGCGCUGGGGCGGCGGAGAGCAUGAGGGAGGCCGGGGGGCGGCUCGGCUUGGAGCGCUGCUAGGGAGCGGUGCGCGCCGCACACCCGCCUGGGCGCGGCGGAGGGCGGGGAGCCGGGCAGGUCGCGCCUGCGGGCGGCAGCCGACCGCCGGGAGCUGUUCUGAUUUCCGACGCGCACGCUAGGGGCCCGGAGCAGCCCCCGGCCCCGGCGCGCCGCCGACAUGGGCAACGCAGGGAGCAUGGAUUCGCAGCAGACCGAUUUCAGGGCGCACAACGUGCCUUUGAAGCUGCCGAUGCCAGAGCCAGGUGAACUGGAGGAGCGAUUUGCCAUCGUGCUGAAUGCUAUGAACCUACCUCCUGACAAAGCCAGGUUACUGCGGCAGUAUGAUAAUGAGAAAAAAUGGGAACUGAUUUGUGAUCAGGAACGAUUCCAGGUGAAGAAUCCUCCCCAUACAUACAUUCAAAAGCUCAAAGGCUAUCUGGAUCCAGCUGUAACCAGGAAGAAAUUCAGACGGCGUGUUCAAGAAUCUACACAAGUGCUAAGAGAACUGGAAAUUUCUUUGAGAACUAACCACAUUGGAUGGGUCAGAGAAUUUCUGAAUGAAGAAAACAAAGGUCUUGAUGUUCUAGUGGAAUAUCUCUCAUUUGCACAGUACGCGGUAACUUUUGACUUUGAAAGUGUGGAGAGUACUGUGGAGAGCUCGGUGGACAAAUCAAAGCCCUGGAGUAGGUCCAUCGAGGACCUGCACAGAGGGAGCAACCUGCCCUCACCUGUGGGCAACAGUGUCUCCCGCUCUGGAAGACAUUCUGCACUGCGAUAUAAUACAUUGCCAAGCAGAAGAACUCUGAAAAAUUCAAGAUUAGUGAGUAAGAAAGAUGAUGUGCAUGUCUGUAUCAUGUGUUUACGUGCCAUCAUGAAUUAUCAGUAUGGUUUCAACAUGGUCAUGUCUCAUCCACACGCUGUCAAUGAGAUUGCACUAAGCCUGAACAACAAGAAUCCCAGAACAAAAGCCCUUGUCUUAGAACUGUUGGCAGCCGUUUGUCUUGUCAGAGGCGGGCAUGAAAUCAUUUUAUCAGCAUUUGAUAACUUUAAAGAGGUUUGUGGAGAAAAACAGCGCUUUGAGAAGUUGAUGGAACAUUUCAGGAAUGAAGACAAUAACAUAGAUUUUAUGGUGGCUUCUAUGCAGUUUAUUAAUAUUGUAGUCCAUUCAGUAGAAGAUAUGAAUUUCAGAGUUCACCUGCAGUAUGAAUUUACCAAAUUAGGCCUGGACGAAUACUUGGACAAGCUGAAACACACUGAGAGUGACAAGCUUCAAGUCCAGAUCCAGGCUUACCUGGACAAUGUUUUUGAUGUAGGAGCUCUACUGGAAGAUGCUGAAACUAAGAAUGCUGCCUUGGAGAGGGUGGAAGAACUGGAAGAAAACAUUUCUCAUUUAUCUGAAAAACUGCAAGACACAGAGAAUGAAGCCAUGUCCAAGAUUGUGGAACUGGAAAAGCAACUCAUGCAGAGGAACAAGGAGCUGGAUGUCGUUCGGGAAAUCUACAAAGAUGCAAAUACUCAAGUUCACACAUUAAGAAAAAUGGUCAAAGAAAAAGAAGAAGCAAUUCAAAGACAGUCUACCCUGGAAAAAAAGAUUCAUGAGCUAGAGAAACAAGGGACCAUUAAAAUUCAGAAGAAAGGGGAUGGGGAUAUCGCCAUACUGCCAGUUGUGGCUUCUGGCACAUUGUCCAUGGGGUCAGAAGUGGUAGCAGGUAACUCUGUGGGACCCACAAUGGGGGCCGCUUCCUCAGGACCCUUGCCCCCUCCUCCACCACCACUGCCUCCCUCAUCAGACACACCUGAAACAGUGCAAAAUGGUCCAGUAACACCACCUAUGCCACCGCCGCCGCCGCCCCCUCCUCCACCUCCUCCUCCCCCACCGCCCCCUCCGCCUCCUCCUCUCCCAGGCCCUGCAGCUGAGACUGUACCAGCUCCUCCCUUAGCACCUCCCCUUCCCUCUGCACCUCCGCUGCCUGGAACAUCUUCACCCACAGUGGUUUUCAACUCAGGAUUAGCAGAUGGGCCAAUCAAGCUUUUCUCUGUGAAAAUUAAGAAGCCAAUCAAGACGAAGUUCAGAAUGCCAGUGUUUAACUGGGUUGCUCUGAAGCCCAAUCAGAUCAAUGGCACAGUCUUCAAUGAAAUUGAUGAUGAGCGAAUUCUGGAGGAUUUAAAUGUGGAUGAAUUUGAGGAAAUAUUCAAGACAAAAGCCCAAGGACCUGCCAUUGAUCUUUCUUCAAGCAAACAGAAGAUACCACAGAAGGGAUCAAACAAAGUGACAUUACUAGAAGCAAACAGGGCCAAAAAUCUUGCCAUAACUUUAAGGAAAGCUGGAAAGACUGCUGAUGAAAUAUGUAAAGCUAUUCAUGUAUUUGACUUGAAGACACUGCCUGUGGACUUUGUGGAAUGCUUGAUGCGGUUCCUACCAACUGAGAAUGAAGUGAAAGUGCUUCGGCUCUACGAGCGGGAAAGGAAGCCUCUGGAAAACUUGUCAGAUGAAGAUCGGUUCAUGAUGCAGUUUAGUAAAAUCGAGAGGCUCAUGCAGAAGAUGACCAUCAUGGCCUUCAUUGGGAACUUUGCUGAAAGCAUUCAGAUGCUGACUCCUCAACUACAUGCGAUUAUAGCAGCAUCUGUCUCUAUAAAGUCGUCCCAAAAACUCAAGAAAAUUCUGGAGAUCAUCUUAGCCCUUGGAAACUACAUGAAUAGCAGUAAAAGAGGAGCAGUUUAUGGAUUUAAACUUCAGAGUUUAGAUCUGCUCUUAGAUACAAAGUCAACAGACAGAAAGCAAACACUGUUGCACUAUAUAUCCAAUGUGGUGAAAGAAAAAUAUCACCAAGUGUCCCUGUUUUAUAAUGAGCUUCAUUAUGUGGAAAAAGCUGCUGCAGUCUCCCUUGAGAAUGUUUUGCUGGAUGUCAAGGAGCUCCAGAGGGGAAUGGACUUGACCAAGAGAGAGUACACCAUGCAUGACCAUAACACGCUGCUGAAGGAGUUCAUCCUCAACAAUGAGGGGAAGCUGAAGAAGCUGCAGGAUGAUGCCAAGAUCGCACAGGAUGCCUUUGAUGAUGUUGUGAAGUAUUUUGGAGAAAACCCCAAGACAACACCACCCUCUGUCUUCUUUCCUGUCUUUGUCCGGUUUGUGAAAGCAUAUAAGCAAGCAGAAGAGGAAAAUGAGCUGAGGAAAAAGCAGGAACAAGCUCUCAUGGAAAAACUCCUAGAGCAAGAAGCUCUGAUGGAGCAGCAGGAUCCAAAGUCUCCUUCUCAUAAAUCAAAGAGGCAGCAGCAAGAGUUAAUUGCAGAAUUAAGAAGACGACAAGUUAAAGAUAACAGACAUGUAUAUGAGGGAAAAGAUGGUGCCAUUGAAGAUAUUAUCACAGCCUUAAAGAAGAAUAAUAUCACUAAAUUUCCAAAUGUUCACUCGAGGGUAAGGAUUUCUUCUAGCACACCGGUGGUGGAGGAUACACAGAGCUGAUCUUAGAAACCAACCAUACAGACGAGCCGAUGCGGUGAGGAGAAGCGUCAGGCGGCGCUUUGAUGAUCAGAACUUGCGUUCUGUUAAUGGUGCCGAAAUAACAAUGUGAACCUGAGACUGGCCUGCAUGAAUACAGGGUGUGCGUGAAUGAAACUGCCCACAUGAACUUUAUGUGCUACGAUUUAACUGCAGCCUUGAACACACACAAAAAUAUUCUUAAGGGCUCAGAUUUAGCAAACACGGAAGAAUUUUAAAAUGAGCUCUCCUUUCAACCCUUGUUAACAAGUGCCUAAAAAUGGAAGUACCUGUUCAGAUUAAUCAAAGCAAUAGGAUUUGAUUUGAUUAGGUAUCUUUUUACACCAGUAUGUUAUUUUUAACCAAAAUGUAAAGUUCUUAUUAAACUCAUUACCUGCCAUUGUGAUUGUCCCAUCAUGGCCCACCUGGUUUCCUGAUGUUGUAAAUAACAUCAAUGCAUCUGCUGUGGGUCCUUUGCUGAGAUGUCUUCGAAGGAAUUUUGUUUUAGCCAUAUCCAUCAACUUUGUAUUUUACUUGCAAUUUGGAAGAAGGAAAGUCACAUGAUGAAACUCCUUUUGUCUAUAACCAGGCCCUGGCAAAGUGCAAACAGGAUGCAACUGCAGUGGCACAAAGGUCACUCAAUCCUUUGUUUCCAGUUUCACAUUCUACUACUUCUGCGCUAGAGAACGAUGCUCUGUGAGAGGCAUUCACUAGUAUGAAUGUGGGGAUAUAGUGUAUAAGACUUAUUUGCAGUACUGUGUUCUUCAGCUAGAGGCAGCUUUUUAAAUAAUGCAAGUGUAUUUAUUAGCAUUAAAAUUAACAUCUCAGUAAUCAGCAUUAGCAUUUCUGAGGACCAUUAUUAAUUCUGAGAACAGAAAUUGGUGCCUUGCAAGGAAGUUUACUAGCUCUAUCAACAAGCAUUCAAGGUUACAUCUGCUAGCAGAGUAGUGUUAGGAACCUGGCCUUACUCUCCUCUGACAAUCGCAAUUUUUUCUUAUUUUUUAUAAAUUCAAGAAGAUACACUUGGCAUCGUGUAUCGAGGCUAAGUUUUUCAUGCAUUUCCCAGACUACUUAUGGAGAAUUGCAGUUUAAGUUGCUGAAAAGUAUUAACAUGGUAUUAAGCUUAAAUAAUACGUAAUGGGACUAGAUGGCCCACUAAGCCACUGUUAUUUUCCUUCCUCUCUGGCAGGGCACUUGAUCCAUUCCAAAGUCAAAAACUGGACUGAAGCUAAAUUUGUACUUUUCAUAAUAUACAUUCUGCUUCUGGCUUAUCUUCUUGGUACAUCAAUAUAUUAAUUGUAAAGUUUAUUGUAUAGUAUUUAACCGCUGAAGUUCCUAUUUUAUGUUGUGCUUAUGUGAACCCCUUGGUGAAGGUCCCUUUUCCUUGGAUGUGUAGUUAUAUGAUCUUUUUAAAUGUACAGAUAUUUUGCUAUAAAAUCGGUGCAGUUUUUUAUGGUUUUUACACUUCUCUUUAAUUCCCACCUAAGCCUCUGGGUAAUAUUGUAAAUAUUGUUUUAAAAUGCAUCAGCCUAUGCUAUACAAUCUGAAUGUUAUUUUAACUUAUAGUUUUUUUUAAUAUAUAUAUUUAACUAUAAGGACAGUUUAGGGAACAAGUUACCUACCACAUUUCACUUUAGUGUACCUAUUUACAGAAAGAUUAAACUGCCACCUGCGGGCACAUUCCCAUAAAUGUGUACUUUACUUUAAAAAGAACAUGCCACGAUUUUGUCUUUCUGUGGACUCAACAUUCACUUCGAUUAAAAAUAGCAAUUUGACCAAGUUGGACUUCCACUACAAAGCAGCUGUUUUCCAAAGUUCAAUGCUGACAUAUAUGUAUAUUAAAAUAAUUGCCUAUUUAUUAAUCUACAAAUAGACAACGUUGGCAUGUUCUUUUCUGUUUGUCUAUUAAUGGGCCUGCUUCUUAGCAAUAUUAGAAUGUUUUAUAAAAGCAAUUCAUGUUACUUUUCUGGUCUUUUCAUGGCAUAUGAGCAAAUAAUAAACUAUUUACACUACUA